AGCCCCUCUACCUCCGGAAGAGACGAGUGCGGUAACACCGUUCACAGAGCUAGCCGGACGUCCUCCGACUCAAGCUCCUAGAAACUUGGUGCAUCCCCAGGCCCAGGUAGUCACUCUAAGUGAUGGGGCAGCGCCCAGGUCCUGUGCUGCCCGCAGUCGCGGUGCUGGGACAGGUGGCAAAAAGGAAGGUGGCCUGGCUCCUACGCUGGAAGGCUGUGACCAGGACAGAAACAGCAGGAAACAGUUCAGGUGUUUAUGGCUUUGGGAAAAUGAAAAUAUUUGUCAAAUAUUUUCAGAAGAUGGCUGAUCCUUGGCAGGAAUGCAUGGAUUAUGCAGUAACUCUAGCAAGACAAGCUGGAGAGGUAGUUUGUGAAGCUAUAAAAAAUGAAAUGAAUGUUAUGCUGAAAAGUUCUCCAGUUGAUUUGGUAACUGCUACGGACCAAAAAGUUGAAAAAAUGCUUAUCUCUUCCAUAAAGGAAAAGUAUCCAUCUCACAGUUUCAUUGGUGAAGAAUCUGUGGCAGCUGGGGAAAAAAGUAUCUUAACCGACAACCCCACAUGGAUCAUUGACCCUAUUGAUGGAACAACUAACUUUGUACAUAGAUUUCCUUUUGUAGCUGUUUCAAUUGGCUUUGCUGUAAAUAAAAAGAUAGAAUUUGGAGUUGUGUACAGUUGUGUGGAAGGCAAGAUGUACACUGCCAGAAAAGGAAAAGGUGCCUUUUGUAAUGGUCAAAAACUACAAGUUUCACAACAAGAAGAUAUUACCAAAUCUCUCUUGGUGACUGAGUUGGGCUCUUCCAGAACACCAGAGACUGUGAGAAUGGUUCUUUCUAAUAUGGAAAAGCUUUUUUGCAUUCCUGUUCAUGGGAUCCGGAGUGUUGGAACAGCAGCUGUUAAUAUGUGCCUUGUGGCAACUGGCGGAGCAGAUGCAUAUUAUGAAAUGGGAAUUCACUGCUGGGAUGUUGCAGGAGCUGGCAUUAUUGUUACUGAAGCUGGUGGCGUGCUAAUGGAUGUUACAGGUGGACCAUUUGAUUUGAUGUCACGAAGAGUAAUUGCUGCAAAUAAUAGAAUAUUAGCAGAAAGGAUAGCUAAAGAAAUUCAGGUUAUACCUUUGCAACGAGACGACGAAGAUUAAUUAAGGCAGCCUCAUAGUCAAUCCCAGUUGCUUUUCCCCAGAUUUGGUGACUCAUCAAUGGAUAUGUGUUUUGGAUGUAUGAUAUGCUUGGUUUAAAUUCUCUUUGUCCAGGUCAAAAAUUUGGAACUUGUUUCUUAUUUUACUAUGUCUAGGUUUGCAAGAAUUGACAUAAUGUUUGUUUCACUGAUUUAAAAAAUUUUGCAUGUAAGAAUGUACUUUAGGAAACAUACCCAGGAAGUACAGUUGAUAAAUAUAACAUCAACUGAAAUAGUCAAUUAGCAAUUUUGUGUUUCUAAAUAUCUAUGGUCCCCUGAAAUUUUGACUUAGUAUAUAGGUGCAGAGACACCCACUUAGAAAGUUAACUGUUUGGAAAAACAUUUCUCUUUAGUUUCAAAAACCAUAUAUAAUUAAAUUUGUAAGGAUAUACUGAGUACCCUAGGCCAACUUUUUUUUCUUUGCAGAGAACCUUUUUUGUUUUAUUCUUCAGUGUUCAUAUAGCACCUGGCCCAUUACAUAUCUAGGCAACUAAAAACAAACAUUGUAAGAAUGAAUAUUUUUAAUGUAGUAAUUCCUAGUUACAAUAGAUACAUAAAGUAAUGAACUCAGCAUUCUGUACUUUUGCUUCAGGUUUGAAGUAAAAAUUAUCUAGUUAAAUUUUUUUUAUUUCACGUUACCAUGCCAUUUCACAUUACCAUACCAUCAGAUAGCAUGGCUUAUUGUGGGCAUUUCUGCAGUGAAUACAUUUUCCAAAACAGUUAAAUUGUCUGUUUGGAUUUGCUUUAAAGUCUUGUGUAAGAGAGAAGAAACUAUUUCUAUAAUAAAAAGCACUCUCAUCAGAUAUCUGACAUAAUUAGAUACAAUAUAACAUUUUACUAAGUUCAGUAUUCAUGUUUUAAAGGUGUUUAUACUGAUUUGAUUGUGCUGGCAAAUAUACUGUAUUGUUAAUAUUGAACUGUUUAUUUUUCUCUUAGUCUUCUUAUUUAAUUAACUUCAUUGCCGCUGGAUUCUGUUCAGCCUUUAAAAAUAUUUCUUAGUGGUCAUUGCUCUGCAGAACUCAAAAAGAAAAUUGUACUUGUUCAUAGACAUUUUUAAAGGGUUAAUUUAUUGUUCAGCCUUAUCCCUUGGCACGUAAACAGACUACUAGACUUAUUGUAGGUUCGUUUGAGCUUUGUGUUGUAAAAUUAAAAAUGCUUCUGUAAAGUUUUCAAGGUAGGGAGUGAUUUUAUUAUUGUGUAUAUCUAAUAUAUUAAGUAUGUGUGAUACUAAGGUUUGACUGCUAUAAUUAUUUGUACUGUUGAUCACAUGUACUUAAAACAUCUGAUACUGUAUUCUAAGACAGGUUGUUUUUGCAAUUAAAUUUAUUUUAAUAAGACGAUCAUGAAUAAAACUUUAAAUUGAUAUUUUUAUUAUUAUUACCAUUAUCAUUAUUAUUAUUUUUAGAUUCAGGGUCUCGCUCUGUUGCCCAGGGUCUGUCUCUGACUGUGCUGUGGUGCAGUCAUAGCUCACUGUAUCCUUAAAUUCCUGGGCUCAAGUGAUCCUCCUCUUUCAGUCUCCUGAGUAGCUGGGACUAUAAGUUCAUGCCACCAUGCCCUACUAAUGUUUUAAUUUUAUUUUUGUAAAGAUGGGAUCUUCCUAUGUUUUCCAGGCCCCUUGGCCUCCCAAAGUGCUGGGAUUACAGAUGUGAGCCACCGAGCCAGGCCAUGAUAUUUACAUUAUUAAAGUUAAUAGUUCAAACUACUUUUAGAGGCUUUGUUUUGUUUUUGUUUUUUGAAGACAGUGUCUUGCUCUUCUGCUCAAACAGUAAUGCAGUGGCAUGAUCACCAUUCAUUGCAGUCUCAACCUUCUGGGCUCAAGCAGUCCUCCCACCUCAGCCUCCCUAGUAACUGGAACCACAGGCACAUGCCACCAUGCCUGGCUAAUUUUUUAGUUUUUGUAGAGACAGAAUCUUCCUAUGUUGCUUAGGCUGGUCUCAUUGGGCUCAAGUGAUCCUCCUGCCUCAGCCUUCUAAAGUGCUGGGAUUACAGAUGUGAGCCAUUGCACCCAACAUACUUUUAGAGGUUUUUGUGUUGAGUUACAAAUAUUUGAAACUUGCAAAUGUAAUUUAAUAUAUGUUCUUAUUUUUUGCCUGUAAUCUUUCCAACUUUUCUAAAAACCUAUAUUUUUUUCUACAAUAGCUUUUCCAUCUGUUUAUUCUAAAUGCAGUUGCAUAUUUUGUGUCUGAAAUUUCUUUAGAUGCUGAAAAAGGAUGAUCGACAAGUGAAUUAUCUAAUAAUAUUUGAAAAUAUUUCUUUGAGUAACAGGACUUCUUAGACUUAACAUGUAUAUUUUGUAUCAGGGUAUAUUAUCUUUCUGCAUGUGGAUACAUACACAGAUACAUACAUAAAUAUACAUAAAUAUAUGUACUUGAACACAUAAAAUAUAUGUACUUGCCUUUUAA